GACUUCGCGGGAGUCGCCGGCGGAGGCGAGGAGGAGCUCUGCGCGGCGCGGCGGGCGAUCCGAGCCGGGACGGGCUGCAGGCGGGGGUGCUGCAGAGGACACGAGGCGGCGGGCUGGAGACAUGGACCGCGGCGAGCAAGGUCUGCUGAGAACAGACCCAGUCCCUGAGGAAGGAGAAGAUGUUGCUGCCACGAUCAGUGCCACAGAGACCCUCUCGGAAGAGGAGCAGGAAGAGCUAAGAAGAGAACUUGCAAAGGUAGAAGAAGAAAUCCAGACUCUGUCUCAAGUGUUAGCAGCAAAAGAGAAGCAUCUAGCAGAGAUCAAGCGGAAACUUGGAAUCAAUUCUCUACAGGAACUAAAACAGAACAUUGCCAAAGGGUGGCAAGACGUGACAGCAACAUCUGCUUACAAGAAGACAUCUGAAACCUUAUCCCAGGCUGGACAGAAGGCCUCAGCUGCUUUUUCGUCUGUUGGCUCAGUCAUCACCAAAAAGCUGGAAGAUGUAAAAAACUCCCCAACUUUUAAAUCAUUUGAAGAAAAGGUCGAAAACUUAAAGGGUUCUCCAAAAAAUGUGGAAUCCUUUGCAUCUAUGCUGAGACAUUCUCCUCUUACACAGAUGGGACCUGCAAAGGAUAAACUGGUCAUUGGACGGAUCUUUCAUAUUGUGGAGAAUGAUCUGUACAUAGAUUUUGGUGGAAAGUUUCAUUGUGUAUGUAGAAGACCAGAAGUGGAUGGAGAGAAAUACCAGAAAGGAACCAGGGUCCGGUUGCGGCUAUUAGAUCUUGAACUUACGUCUAGGUUCCUGGGAGCAACAACAGAUACAACUGUACUAGAGGCUAAUGCAGUUCUCUUGGGAAUCCAGGAGAGUAAAGACUCAAGAUCGAAAGAAGAACAUCAUGAAAAAUAAAUGAACUUUGCUUAGUGGAUUGACUCCUUUGCUGAAGUCAGUUAUUCAUCAAGAAUGCAAUUAGACUAAUUGUGAAUAAAUGAUUGAAUGAAGAUAUAAUAAAUAAAAGCUAUAAUUAUAGAUAACUCUUAUUAGAAUUUUCUUUAGCAAUAUUCCCACCCCCCACCCCUUGUUUUGCUCUUAAUGUUUUUUUCCUUUGGUGGGGAUAGUAUACACUGUACUAAGAAAUUGUCAUUCAAUAAAUACGUUUUGAGUGCUGUCUA